CACUUCCGUCGAGCAGCCAAUAUAUGCCUCAUUCUGCAGCAGGUAAUCUAAGAUAGAUGUAACAGAAGCAAUAUUAAGAAUUAGCAGAUAUGCUACGUGUAGUGGAAGGCAUCUUCAUUUUUGUUGUAGUUAGUGAGUCAGUGUUUGGGGUUUUGGGGAAUGGAUUUAUUGGACUUGUAAACUGCAUUGACUGUGCCAAGAAUAAGUUAUCUACGAUUGGCUUUAUUCUCACCGGCUUAGCUAUUUCAAGAAUUUUUCUGAUAUGGAUAAUAAUUACAGAUGGAUUUAUACAGAUAUUCUCUCCAAAUAUAUAUGCCUCCGGUAACCUAAUUGAAUAUAUUAGUUACUUUUGGGUAAUUGGUAAUCAAUCAAGUAUGUGGUUUGCCACCAGCCUCAGCAUCUUCUAUUUCCUGAAGAUAGCAAAUUUUUCCAACUACAUAUUUCUCUGGUUGAAGAGCAGAACAAAUAUGGUUCUUCCCUUCAUGAUAGUAUUCUUACUUAUUUCAUCGUUACUUAAUUUUGCAUACAUUGCGAAGAUUCUUAAUGAUUAUAAAACGAAGAAUGACACAGUCUGGGAUCUCAACAUGUAUAAAAGUGAAUACUUUAUUAAACAGAUUUUGCUAAAUCUGGGAGUCAUUUUCUUCUUUACACUAUCCCUAAUUACAUGUAUUUUUUUAAUCAUUUCCCUUUGGAGACACAACAGGCAGAUGCAAUCGAAUGUGACAGGAUUGAGAGACUCCAACACAGAAGCUCAUGUGAAGGCAAUGAAAGUUUUGAUAUCUUUCAUCAUCCUCUUUAUCUUGUAUUUUAUAGGCAUGGCCAUAGAAAUAUCAUGUUUUACUGUGCGAGAAAACAAACUGCUGCUUAUGUUUGGAAUGACAACCACAGCCAUCUAUCCCUGGGGUCACUCAUUUAUCUUAAUUCUAGGAAACAGCAAGCUAAAGCAAGCCUCUUUGAGGGUACUGCAGCAAUUGAAGUGCUGUGAGAAAAGGAAAAAUCUCAGAGUCACAUAGACACCUUGGGAAGAGAUGGAUGUUCCACGAAAGGAAUCCAGUGAAUAAAUCCUUGAAGAUCUGUUUCAUUGCACUGCAUUCUUGCAUUGUCUUUUUAACUGUGUCAUUAAAGAUCACUGAAAUCUUC